GUCUUUUAUUUUGUUUUCCACCAUGCCUGAACCAGUCAAAUCUGCUCCAGUCCCUAAAAAAGGCUCCAAGAAGGCCAUUAACAAGGCUCAGAAGAAGGAUGGAAAGAAGCGCAAACGCAGCCGCAAGGAGAGCUACUCUGUGUAUGUGUACAAGGUGCUGAAGCAGGUCCACCCCGACACCGGCAUCUCUUCCAAGGCUAUGGGAAUCAUGAACUCCUUCGUCAACGACAUCUUUGAGCGUAUCGCCGGAGAAGCGUCACGCCUGGCGCAUUACAACAAGCGCUCGACCAUCACUUCGAGGGAGAUCCAGACGGCCGUGCGCCUACUGCUACCCGGGGAAUUGGCCAAGCACGCCGUGUCCGAGGGCACCAAGGCCGUCACCAAGUAUACCAGCUCCAAGUGAGCCUCUCGCUGCAGUAACAGUUCCGCCGUGACCCACACCCCAAAGGCUCUUUUCAGAGCCGUCCA